GCAACGGCGCGGUGGCCUGGAACCCCAGGGGAGUGGUGGGCGGGGCCUGAAGUACCCAAGUCCCCGAGGGCGCGCCUUCCCCGGGAAUUUAAUUCAGGACAAUAAUGUUUUAUUGAGCGCCUAUUGUGAAUCAGACACUGAGCAGUAAGCGUCGGAGAAACAGGUGAAUGAUACCGGGGAAAAGUCAUUCCCUGUGUGUAGCGUCUAGGGCAGCCUUUGCCCUGGUUCCAGCAGAUGGGUUGUCUCUUCAUAGUCUAUGCAUUUCUGAAGACCCCACGGUGAAGGGCUGCAAGGAUGAAGCUGUCCCAGAGUAUCUCCAGAGUGCAGAUCCCUUGGCUGCCAGGUCAUGUUCUCUCUUCCUCUCAACUGCUCUCCCGACCAUAUAAGGAGAGGCAGCUGCUGGGGGCGUCCCCAGGAUCUAAAGAUAGCGGCCCCUGCCUGGAACUCUAAAUGCCACCCUGGAGCGGGAGCCGCAAUGGCACGGCAGCACGCCCGGACCUUGUGGUACGACAGGCCCAGGUAUGUGUUCAUGGAGUUUUGUGUUGAGGACAGCACCGAUGUCCACGUGCUUAUUGAGGAUCACCGCAUUGUGUUCAGCUGCAAGAAUGCCGAUGGAGUGGAGUUGUACAAUGAGAUUGAGUUCUAUGCCAAAGUGAACUCCAAGGACUCCCAGGAUAAGCGCUCUUCCCGCUCUAUUACUUGUUUUGUGAGAAAAUGGAAGGAAAAGGUGGCCUGGCCGCGGCUUACCAAGGAGGAUAUCAAGCCAGUGUGGCUGUCUGUGGACUUUGAUAACUGGAGAGACUGGGAAGGGGAUGAAGAGAUGGAGCUGGCUCAUGUGGAACAUUAUGCAGAGCUUUUGAAGAAGGUCAGCACCAAGAGACCUCCACCUGCCAUGGAUGAUUUGGAUUUCACCACCACCGUGGUCUCCUGCUGUCCCGCGGAGCUGCAGACUGAAGGGAGCAACGGCAAGAAAGAAGUGCUGAGCGGUUUCCAAGUGGUGCUGGAAGACACAGUGCUUUUCCCUGAGGGCGGGGGACAGCCUGAUGACCGUGGUACAAUCAAUGACAUCUCUGUGCUGAGAGUGACUCGCCGUGGGGAACAGGCUGAUCAUUUCACCCAGACACCCCUGGAUCCAGGAAGCCAGGUUCUGGUCCGGGUAGAUUGGGAGCGGAGGUUUGACCACAUGCAGCAGCAUUCAGGGCAGCAUCUCAUCACGGCAGUUGCUGACCAUCUAUUUAAGCUGAAGACAACAUCAUGGGAGUUAGGGAGAUUUCGGAGUGCGAUUGAGCUGGACACCCCCUCUAUGACUGCAGAGCAAGUAGCUGCCAUUGAGCAGAGCGUCAAUGAAAAAAUCAGAGAUCGGCUGCCUGUGAAUGUCCGAGAACUGAGCCUGGAUGAUCCUGAGGUGGAGCAGGUGAGUGGCCGGGGUUUGCCUGAUGAUCAUGCUGGGCCCAUUCGGGUUGUUAACAUCGAGGGCGUUGAUUCCAACAUGUGCUGUGGGACCCAUGUGAGCAAUCUCAGUGACCUUCAGGUCAUUAAGAUUCUGGGCACUGAGAAGGGGAAAAAGAACAGAACCAACCUGAUAUUUCUGUCUGGGAACCGGGUGCUGAAGUGGAUGGAGAGAAGUCAUGGAACUGAAAAAGCACUGACUGCUCUGCUUAAGUGUGGAGCAGAGGAUCAUGUGGAAGCAGUGAAAAAGCUCCAGAACUCCACCAAGAUCCUGCAGAAGAAUAACCUGAAUCUGCUCAGAGACCUGGCUGUGCACAUUGCCCAUAGCCUCAGGAACAGUCCAGACUGGGGAGGUGUGGUCAUAUUACACAGGAAGGAGGGUGAUUCAGAGUUCAUGAAUAUCAUUGCCAAUGAGAUUGGGUCAGAGGAGACCCUCCUGUUCUUAACUGUGGGCGAUGAGAAAGGUGGUGGACUCUUCUUACUGGCAGGGCCACCUGCGUCUGUGGAGACCCUGGGGCCCAGGGUGGCUGAGGUCCUGGAAGGCAAAGGAGCAGGGAAGAAAGGCCGUUUUCAGGGCAAGGCCACCAAGAUGAGCCGGCGGAUGGAGGCGCAGGCGCUUCUCCAGGACUACAUCAGCACGCAGAGUGCUAAGGAGUGAGGGCUUAGGGCACUCACCUCCUGUUUCCACAGGAAUCUUUUGGUCAAUAAAAUAGAUUGACUCAGAA